ACCGCCUCGUGCCGUACUGGCUUCUGGGUGGCCCUUAAUGUCUUGUGCUCUAAGGUGCUGAGGGGAAAGACGCGGGAGGUCUCUGGCCUGACACUAUGAAGGAAGAGAGAAACUACAACUUCGACGGUGUGAGCACCAACCGCCUGAAACAGCAGUUGCUGGAAGAAGUCCGCAAGAAGUAGUGAAUGGAAAACCCGUUAUGAGACACAACUUGAAUUAAAUGAUGAACUAGAAAAGCAAAUUGUUUAUCUCAAGGAGAAAGUGGAAAAAAUCCAUGGAAACUCUUCAGGAAUCCUUAAACACAUUACUUAAACAGCUAGAAGAAGAAAAGAAGACUCUUGAAAGUCAAGUGAAAUACUAUGCACUUAAACUGGAACAAGAAUCAAAGGCUUACCAGAAGAUCAACAAUGAACGCCGUACAUACCUAGCUGAAAUGUCUCAGGGUUCUGGUUUACAUCAAGUUUCUAAAAGGCAACAGGUGGAUCAACUGCCUAGGAUGCAAGAGAAUCUAGUGAAAACCCUCCUCUUAAAAGAAGAAUUGGACCCUUUAAAGGCAAAAAUAGACAUCUUAUUAGUUGGAGAUGUCACUGUGGGCUACCUGGCUGAUACUGUACAGAAACUAUUUGCAAACAUAGCAGAAGUCACCAUCACCAUCAGUGACACGAAGGAGGCAGCAGCGCUUUUGGAUGAUUGCAUAUUCAACAUGGUUCUCUUGAAGGUGCCUUCUUCACUAAGUGCCGAGGAGCUGGAAGCCAUCAAGUUAAUUAGAUUUGGCAAAAAGAAAAAUACACAUUCACUGUUUGUUUUUAUAAUCCCUGAAAAUUUUAAAGGUUGUAUUUCAGGGCAUGGAAUGGAUAUUGCUUUAACUGAACCACUGACAAUGGAAAAAAUGAGUAAUGUGGUAAAAUACUGGACAACAUGUCCCUCAAACACUGUUAAGACUGAAAACGCAACUGGGCCUGAAGAACUUGGAUUGCCCCUGCAGAGGUCCUACAGCGAACACCUGGGAUAUUUUCCUACUGAUCUAUUUGCCUGCUCUGAAUCUUUAAGGAAUGGCAAUGGGCUUGAAUUAAAUGCUUCGUUGUCAGAGUUCGAGAAAAACAAAAAGAUCUCUCUUCUUCAUUCAAGCAAGGAAAAACUAAGAAGGGAAAGAAUCAAAUAUUGCUGUGAGCAGCUGCGUACUCUCUUGCCGUAUGUAAAAGGGAGAAAGAAUGAUGCGGCUUCAGUUCUUGAGGCAACAGUUGAUUAUGUGAAAUAUAUCCGGGAGAAAAUCUCUCCAGCCGUUAUGGCCCAGAUUACAGAAGCACUUCAGAGCAACAUGAGGUUUUGUAAGAAACAACAAACACCCAUUGAGCUGUCUCUCCCAGGCACUGUCAUGGCACAGCGGGAAAACAGUGUGAUGAGCACUUACUCCCCUGAGAGAGGGCUCCAAUUCCUGACUAAUACGUGCUGGAAUGGGUGCUCCACUCCUGAUGCAGAGAGCUCCUUGGAUGAAGCUGUGAGAGUUCCAUCAAGCUCCGCCUCAGAGAAUGCUAUUGGUGAUCCAUAUAAAACUCACAUUUCCAGUGCAGCGCUGUCUCUGAAUUCCUUGCAUACUGUCAGAUAUUAUUCUAAAGUCACCCCUUCCUACGAUGCAACUGCUGUAACAAAUCAGAACAUUUCAAUUCAUUUACCUUCAGCCAUGCCCCCGGUCUCAAAGCUUCUCCCUCGGCACUGCACUUCUGGGUUGGGCCAGACGUGCACUACACAUCCCAACUGUCUGCAACAGUUUUGGGCGUAUUAAAAGCACAUGUUUGAAAUUCACACUCUCAACCACCUACUGGGCGCAGUUUGACAAUCUAGGAAAAGUGGAACAAAGAAUGAUUUUGAAAGCUCCACCCAAAGACCUAAUAUCAAAAGAGUUGGCAUGGUUUGGCUUCUGAUAAAUGCACUCAAAGCUUCUGCAGAUAGAAAGACCAGCAGCGAAAAAGCUGGCCACACACUGUCACUCAUCUUCAUACACACUUGGAUCCCCGCCAGCCAGAGAGCUACAAGAACAAAUGGCCUCAGUGACCUACACUCUCUUUUCUCAAAAAAUAUUCCACAAUUUAUGAAAAAAGCAUGCUAUAAGGAAGAUCCAUGUAGACACGAUAAAAUGAUUAGAUUGGGAAGGUGUGUUGAUACCUUGUGUCACUGAGUACAGAUAUUACAACUUGAUUCUUAUUUUUAGUAUCCCUGUGAAUUACUGUCACUCAUUUCUAGGUGGUCUUUUCCUUAUUUGACAUUUUAGAGAGUUUCCUUCUUCAUUCACCAUCCAAACUAAGAUAUGCAGAGAGAUGCUGAAAGAGGGGUUUACCUCCUCACUUGACAACUAAUGAAUAAAUUGAUGUGUGCUUUUGCAUUUCACAAUCCCUUGAGUGAAACGAUGGCUAAUAGGUAAAUAUUUCUUUCUGGACCUUAAGUUACAGACUAGCAGGUUUUUUGUUUUUCAUCUCUUCCUCCCUAUGGGUAUUAGAAAGGACAGUUGAAAAUAAGGGGGAAAAAGGUUUGUUUUAUAUUUCACUGAAUUGUUCUUAUAUGUAAGUUUUAUUAUUAAAUAAAAUACUCAGUUUUCACCCUGA